CUUUUCUUUGAAUGACAGAACUACAGCAUAAUGCGUGGCUUCAACCUGCUCCUCUUCUGGGGAUGUUGUGUUAUGCACAGCUGGGAAGGGCACAUAAGACCCACACGGAAACCAAACACAAAGGGUAAUAACUGUAGAGACAGUACCUUGUGCCCAGCUUAUGCCACCUGCACCAAUACAGUGGACAGUUACUAUUGCGCUUGCAAACAAGGCUUCCUGUCCAGCAAUGGGCAAAAUCACUUCAAGGAUCCAGGAGUGCGAUGCAAAGAUAUUGAUGAAUGUUCUCAAAGCCCCCAGCCCUGUGGUCCUAACUCAUCCUGCAAAAACCUGUCAGGGAGGUACAAGUGCAGCUGUUUAGAUGGUUUCUCUUCUCCCACUGGAAAUGACUGGGUCCCAGGAAAGCCGGGCAAUUUCUCCUGUACUGAUAUCAAUGAGUGCCUCACCAGCAGCGUCUGCCCUGAGCAUUCUGACUGUGUCAACUCCAUGGGAAGCUACAGUUGCAGCUGUCAAGUUGGAUUCAUCUCUAGAAACUCCACCUGUGAAGAUAUUGAUGAAUGUUCUCAAAGCCCCCAGCCCUGUGGUCCUAAUUCAUCCUGCAAAAACAUGUCAGGGAGGUACAAGUGCAGCUGUUUAGAUGGUUUCUCUUCUCCCACUGGAAAUGACUGGAUCCCAGGAAAGCCGGGCAAUUUCUCCUGUACUGAUAUCAGUGAGUCCCUCACCAGCAGCGUCUGCCCUGAGCAUUCUGACUGUGUCAACUCCAUGGGAAGCUACAAUUGCAGCUGUCAAGUUGGAUUCAUCUCUAGAAACUCUAUCUCUUCAGACGUGGAUGAAUGUGCAGAUCCAAGAGCUUGCCCAGAGCAUGCAACUUGUAAUAACACUGUUGGAAACUACUCUUGUUUCUGCAACCCAGGAUUUGAAUCCAGCAGUGGCCACUUGAGUUUCCAGGGUCUCAAAGCAUCGUGUGAAGAUAUUGAUGAAUGCACUGAAAUGUGCCCCAUCAAUUCAACAUGCACCAACACUCCUGGGAGCUACUUUUGCACCUGCCACCCUGGCUUUGCACCAAGCAAUGGACAGUUGAAUUUCACAGACCAAGGAGUGGAAUGUAGAGAUAUUGAUGAGUGCCGCCAAGAUCCAUCAACCUGUGGUCCUAAUUCUAUCUGCACCAAUGCCCUGGGCUCCUACAGCUGUGGCUGCAUUGCAGGCUUUCAUCCCAAUCCAGAAGGCUCCCAGAAAGAUGGCAACUUCAGCUGCCAAAGGGUUCUCUUCAAAUGUAAGGAAGAUGUGAUACCCGAUAAUAAGCAGAUCCAGCAAUGCCAAGAGGGAACCGCAGUGAAACCUGCAUAUGUCUCCUUUUGUGCACAAAUAAAUAACAUCUUCAGCGUUCUGGACAAAGUGUGUGAAAAUAAAACGACCGUAGUUUCUCUGAAGAAUACAACUGAGAGCUUUGUCCCUGUGCUUAAACAAAUAUCCACGUGGACUAAAUUCACCAAGGAAGAGACGUCCUCCCUGGCCACAGUCUUCCUGGAGAGUGUGGAAAGCAUGACACUGGCAUCUUUUUGGAAACCCUCAGCAAAUAUCACUCCGGCUGUUCGGACGGAAUACUUAGACAUUGAGAGCAAAGUUAUCAACAAAGAAUGCAGUGAAGAGAAUGUGACGUUGGACUUGGUAGCCAAGGGGGAUAAGAUGAAGAUCGGGUGUUCCACAAUUGAGGAAUCUGAAUCCACAGAGACCACUGGUGUGGCUUUUGUCUCCUUUGUGGGCAUGGAAUCGGUUUUAAAUGAGCGCUUCUUCAAAGACCACCAGGCUCCCUUGACCACCUCUGAGAUCAAGCUGAAGAUGAAUUCUCGAGUCGUUGGGGGCAUAAUGACUGGAGAGAAGAAAGACGGCUUCUCAGAUCCAAUCAUCUACACUCUGGAGAACAUUCAGCCAAAGCAGAAGUUUGAGAGGCCCAUCUGUGUUUCCUGGAGCACUGAUGUGAAGGGUGGAAGAUGGACAUCCUUUGGCUGUGUGAUCCUGGAAGCUUCUGAGACAUAUACCAUCUGCAGCUGUAAUCAGAUGGCAAAUCUUGCCGUUAUCAUGGCGUCUGGGGAGCUCACGAUGGACUUUUCCUUGUACAUCAUUAGCCAUGUAGGCAUUAUCAUCUCCUUGGUGUGCCUCGUCUUGGCCAUCGCCACCUUUCUGCUGUGUCGCUCCAUCCGAAAUCACAACACCUACCUCCACCUGCACCUCUGCGUGUGUCUCCUCUUGGCGAAGACUCUCUUCCUCGCCGGUAUACACAAGACUGACAACAAGAUGGGCUGCGCCAUCAUCGCGGGCUUCCUGCACUACCUUUUCCUUGCCUGCUUCUUCUGGAUGCUGGUGGAGGCUGUGAUACUGUUCUUGAUGGUCAGAAACCUGAAGGUGGUGAAUUACUUCAGCUCUCGCAACAUCAAGAUGCUGCACAUCUGUGCCUUUGGUUAUGGGCUGCCGAUGCUGGUGGUGGUGAUCUCUGCCAGUGUGCAGCCACAGGGCUAUGGAAUGCAUAAUCGCUGCUGGCUGAAUACAGAGACAGGGUUCAUCUGGAGUUUCUUGGGGCCAGUUUGCACAGUUAUAGUGAUCAACUCCCUUCUCCUGACCUGGACCUUGUGGAUCCUGAGGCAGAGGCUUUCCAGUGUUAAUGCCGAAGUCUCAACGCUAAAAGACACCAGGUUACUGACCUUCAAGGCCUUUGCCCAGCUCUUCAUCCUGGGCUGCUCCUGGGUGCUGGGCAUUUUUCAGAUUGGACCUGUGGCAGGUGUCAUGGCUUACCUGUUCACCAUCAUCAACAGCCUGCAGGGGGCCUUCAUCUUCCUCAUCCACUGUCUGCUCAACGGCCAGGUACGAGAAGAAUACAAGAGGUGGAUCACUGGGAAGACGAAGCCCAGCUCCCAGUCCCAGACCUCAAGGAUCUUGCUGUCCUCCAUGCCAUCCGCUUCCAAGACGGGUUAAAGUCCUUUCUUGCUUUCAAAUAUGCUAUGGAGCCACAGUUGAGGACAGUAGUUUCCUGCAGGAGCCUACCCUGAAAUCUCUUCUCAGCUUAACAUGGAAAUGAGGAUCCCACCAGCCCCAGAACCCUCUGGGGAAGAAUGUUGGGGGCGGUCUUCCUGUGGUUGUAUGCACUGAUGAGAAAUCAGGCGUUUCUGCUCCAAACGACCAUUUUAUCUUCGUGCUCUGCAACUUCUUCAAUUCCAGAGUUUCUGAGAACAGACCCAAAUUCAAUGGCAUGACCAAGAACACCUGGCUACCAUUUUGUUUUCUCCUGCCCUUGUUGGUGCAUGGUUCUAAGCAUGCCCCUCCAGAGCCUAUCAUACGCCUGAUACAGAGAACCUCUCAAUAAAUGAUUUGUCGCCUGUCUGACUGAUUUACCCUA